AUAAUAUGCUCCUUUUUCAGGUAAAGAGACGGAGGCUCAGAGAGGUUAAACAGCUCACUCAAAGGCACAGAGCCAGUACAUGGCAGUACAUCUCUUCUCCCGGGGCCGCCGUCGCGGUGAUACUAUUUAGGGCCACACGUCCCAGUGUUCAGCUUUCGUAUUUACGUACUACUGUUUGGCAAGCGGGGACUCCUGAAGCUCUCUGACCCUGGAAAAUGCGUGGCUUGCGUCACAGAGGAGCGUUUCUGGAACGCGCUCGCAGCACGACACCGCGGUGUGUGCAAGCGGAACGCCGCCCUGUCCUUGAGCCUUUUGGCUGAGAUUGGGAGGGCAGAGGAAGCAGGAAGGAUCAGUGAAUGCUUGUGAAAAGACCUCAUUUAUGUUUCUGCGGCAAGAGUUGCCUGUCAGACUGGCAAAUAUAAUGAAAGAAAUAAGUCUCCUUCCAGAUAAUCUUCUCAGGACACCAUCCGUUCAAUUGGUACAAAGCUGGUAUAUCCAGAGUCUUCAGGAGCUUCUUGAUUUUAAGGACAAAAGUGCUGAGGAUGCUAAAGCUAUUUAUGAAAGGCCUAGAAGAACAUGGUUGCAGGUCUCUAGUUUAUGCUGUAUGGCCUGCAAGAUGAUCUUUACAGAUACUGUGAUACGGAUCAGAAACCGACACAAUGAUGUCAUUCCCACAAUGGCCCAGGGUGUGAUUGAAUACAAGGAGAGCUUUGGGGUGGAUCCUGUCACCAGCCAGAAUGUUCAGUACUUUUUGGAUCGAUUCUACAUGAGUCGCAUUUCAAUUAGAAUGUUACUCAAUCAGCACUCUUUAUUGUUUGGUGGAAAAGGCAAAGGAAGUCCAUCUCAUCGAAAACACAUUGGAAGCAUAAAUCCAAACUGCAAUGUACUUGAAGUUAUUAAAGAUGGCUAUGAAAAUGCUAGGCGUCUGUGUGAUUUGUAUUAUAUUAACUCUCCCGAACUAGAACUUGAAGAACUAAAUGCAAAAUCACCAGGACAGCCAAUACAAGUGGUUUAUGUACCAUCCCAUCUCUAUCACAUGGUGUUUGAACUUUUCAAGAAUGCAAUGAGAGCCACUAUGGAACACCAUGCCAACAGAGGUGUUUACCCCCCUAUUCAAGUUCAUGUCACGCUGGGUAAUGAGGAUUUGACUGUGAAGAUGAGUGACCGAGGAGGUGGCGUUCCUUUGAGGAAAAUUGACAGACUUUUCAACUACAUGUAUUCAACUGCACCAAGACCUCGUGUUGAGACCUCCCGCGCAGUGCCUCUGGCUGGUUUUGGUUAUGGAUUGCCCAUAUCACGUCUUUACGCACAAUACUUCCAAGGAGACCUGAAGCUGUAUUCCCUAGAGGGUUACGGGACAGAUGCAGUUAUCUACAUUAAGGCUCUGUCAACAGACUCAAUAGAAAGACUCCCAGUGUAUAACAAAGCUGCCUGGAAGCAUUACAACACCAACCACGAGGCUGAUGACUGGUGCGUCCCCAGCAGAGAACCCAAAGACAUGACGACGUUCCGCAGUGCCUAGACACACUUGGGACAUCGGAAAAUCCAAAUGUGGCUUUUGUAUUAAAUUUGGAAGGUAUGGUGUUCAGAACUAUAUUAUACCAAGUACUUUAUUUAUCGUUUUCACAAAACUAUUUGAGUAGAAUAAAUGGAAACUGAAUUCCAUUUGUGCCCGUUAAACCUCCUAAAGGAUGAAAUUGCACCUAUUUUACACUUAUAUUUUCACAGUUAAUUGAACAUAUUUUUAAACAACUGUAGUUUUGGGCAACUUUUCACUUUGUGGUAGACUUCAGAAGUGUGGAAAUCUUCGGGUUUCUAUAGGAAACUAGUUUUUUUUUUUUAAGAAAUACUUUCAUUUAUGUUUGCUAGAAACAUUUUCUAAAUGAUAGUGAUUAGCUGGUUAGCCAUCUUCCUGUUAUUUGGAGGAGUUCUGCCAUCUUUUAUUCGGUAGUGACAGCUGUAAUAUGGUCUUCAUGUUUAUCAGUGACUUGACUACAAGUAAAGCAGAAAACAGUUGGCCUGUAAUCACAGAACCAGCCACCCUUCGGCGUCUACAUGCAUUGUCUUAGCUCUGAGGUUAAUUUACCAUUUUUAAAUUUUAUUGUAAAGAAGUGUAAUGACUAGCUCUCUGUGGAUCUAUGCCAAAAUCAUGGGCCAUCUUUUCUAAGUGUACUUCUGAUUAAUGCAAGGGGAAAUUUUUAUACUGAAAACAAACAAACAAACUAGCAGCUACUAAAAUAGAGAAGAAAUUGAGGGCAAAGUAAUAUGUCUCCAAAACUGAACUGAUUGCUUGUUGAGAUUACCUAGAAAGCUUUUGGAAAAAAAUAGAGCUUUUCUGCAUCCUACUCCAGAUACACUGAAUCGGAAUCCCUAGGGCUAGAGCCUAGAAAUCUCACUUUUUAAAAUGCUUCCAAGGUAAGUCUGAUGCCUACCCUAGGUUGGGAACCACUCUUUCAAAGUAAACAGUGAUGACACAGCAUUUGCUAAAGUAACAUCUGUAGGUUUUGGUUUCCACCUAUUUAAAGUCAGAUUUAUAGACUCGAGGAGACAGAAACUGAAUCCCACACCUGGUGCAAUUAGAAGCAUAAUUAGAAGCAGAAGAACAAAAUGCCACGUAACCAAAGCAUCAGAGCCAUCAUUGCACGUGUCUUUUUUUCUUUUUUCUUUUUUUUUUUUCAAGACAGGGUCUCGCUCUUUUGCCCAGGAUGGAGUACAGUGGCAUGGUCAAGGCUCACUGCAGCUUCAAUCUUCUGGGCUCAAGUAAUCCUUCCACCUCAGCCUCCCAUAUAGCUGGAACUACAGUUGUGCACUACCACACCCAGCUAAUUUUUUGAUUUCUUGUGGAGAUGAGGUCUCAGUAUGUUCCCAGGCUAGUGUUGAACUCCUGAGCUCAAGAAAUCCUCCUGCCUGAGUCUCUGAAAGUGCUGGGAUUACAGGCGUGAGCCACCACACAUGGCCUAUUGCACAAGUCUUGACAAACAACAUAUAUUUUCUAAAACUAUCCAGAUUUCAUUAUCAGGGAAAAGUUUGCUUAGGUUUAUUACAGCAGUCCUUGGCAUUUGUAUGGUAAUUUGUACUUUACAAAUACUUUGAUAUAUUAUAACUCUAUUGGUCUUUGAAACAAAGCGAUACAGUGUAGGUGGUAUCAUUCUCUUUCUCACUCAGUGUGGCCCAGAGUUGCUCAGAAUUGGAGCAGAGCCUGAGACGUAUCUGCAGAUCCUGUCAUCAGCUGGCAAGUCCAGGAGACUGUGUCAUUUAGAGACUGUGUUGUUAGUUAUCCCUCAACAUCUUCUAAGGUGGCAGGAAAUAAUAUUGGAAAUAACAUUUUAAAGUAAAAAUUUUAAAGUUUAAAGAAGAGUUUUGCCACUUAAACAGGGGAGCUUUGUCUGGAAAAUACACUGAGUUGAAACACUUCAUCCUUGGAAGGAUUAUAUAAGAUGAACAGUUGUGAUAAAUGUGUAGAUUAGAGGGAUGUGAAUGGGCAGUUAGUCCAGUGCCCUCAUUUAAGAGGCCAAGAUCCUGAUUCAGAGGAGGCAUCCUUUGCCCAGAGCUGCUUAGCUAAUCUGACCAAAUGUUGGGAAAAAUGUCUCACCUAACCCACUAUUCCUUAAUUAUGGAUUUUGUGAAAAACAAUAGAACAUGUUAAUGAGUAAUUUAUAUUAGUUCGAUGUAUUACAAUUUUUUAGCUUUAAAUUACAGUUUUCUUAUAAUGUUGAAAUGUUUUAGAAUCCUUUGAAUCUAAGUAUUUGUUUCCUAAAUGAAACAUUUGUACAACAUUUGAUGUUUUUACUUAUGAAAUAUUCUCCUCCCCCAAGAAAAUUUAAACUUUUUCUCUCUAUUUAAAAGCUAAGAAAUGUUUUAAAGGAAAAAUGAAAUUAUCUUCCUUUAGCUUAUUUUUAAGGUAAAACAGCUUUUUACUCUGUUAUUGUGGUAAUGGACAGAAUAUUACAUACAAAAAUAUUCUGGGAGAGCUUUUUCCUAGUUGGUUUUAAAUCAUUGUGCCACCUGAAAGGUUUUUAGAUUUUAUAGGAGCUAAUUUGUCCACCAGCAUUAAUGUAACACAGUGUAGUUAUGAAAAUAUAUUGAAGGACAGGAAGUGGACACGAAGUGAUUUUUGUAACCUGAGCAGUUAAUGAAUGUGCCAACAUUUUCUAGGAAGGGACAGCAAGAAUAUUCUGCUCUGUAGUUAAAAUACUGGCUGGCUUUUGAUGUCUUCAUGCUUAAUUGUGAUCACUUUCUUGCACUGUGAUGUUUUUACGUGAAUAUGUUGAAGUAGAAGUCUACCAUAUUAUUUUAUAAAAUGUUUUCUGUAUGGCAAUAAACUGAAAACAUGGAUCAACCCUUCUUUUGAAAAUAAACUGAGUCAAUUUAGCCUUUUAAAAAUAUAGUCAUCUCUUUUAAAUAGAAUCCUCUUCCACCAUCAAGGCUCAACAUUUUGUAAGCAUCCAAAAAAUUGGUAAUUAGGGGGCUUGCACUAAAUUUCACUAUCUUCAGUAGAGAGGAACUGUUUGGAACUUAGAUUUCCAAUGUGUAUAUUCUAAUGGAGAAAGCAAGAGGUAGAGUUUGUAUGUUUGACUUACCUUAGAUUUUUAUUUUCCAUACAUACUGCAAAUGAUUGACUUGUUGCAUAAAUGAAGAUCUUCUGUUGUGUGCUUUUCAAACACUGUAAAUAAAUUUGAAAUUUGAAUAACUUUCCACAGUAUAACUGUAAAAAAAAAAAAAAAAAGUCUUAAUUUAACCAGCAUUACCCUCUGCUUGUACCAAUUGAAUGGCAGAACUACUAUAGUCAAAAAUAAAUUCCUAUCCUAUUUUUAAUUGAUGGGAUAUAGGCAGCACAAUUUCCCUUCAUUGUUGAAGCCAACAAGUUCCGUAACAGAACUCCAGAGGUAAAUAGCUGGGAAAACUGUUAGUUUUAAGGUCCCACUGUUGCUCUGUGAAUGACUAAUCAGAGGAAGCCAAAAAUCAGCCAACUAAUUUCAGUUUAUGUCUUUAAUUGUGAUGUAAGUGUGAAGUUUCUACAUAUGGGUAAUCAGGGUUGAGUUAGGUAGUUUGCAAACAUGACUUUUGCUGGAGGAACUUUUAAUCAUGUCUUAUUAAUUUCUGGUCCCAAUAAUUAAUUUUCUUACAGUCAAACCCAAUGCACUUGAAAAAUAAUAUAAUUAAUACUGUGUGAAGAAUUUUUUGCAUGUUAAAAAAAGCAAACCACUAGUUUGCUUAGUUCUGGCAUUCAUAAACUACUGUACCUUCUGUUCUAUUGACAUGUUUGGAAAAAAGAAUUGAACAUAUGUACCACCCCCCUCUUUCUAGAGUCUCCACAGUUCUUUAGCAAUUGCUAACCAUAGGUUUUUAAUAGCAAAAGACAAGAUUGUCAGUUUUUGGUGCAAAACUCUACUCUUUUUGGUUGACUUGGAAAAGCUGUUGUUUAUAUUGGGAAUUGUGACAGCUGUCUUUUACUUUGUUAAAUUAGCAAUUAUUUAGCAAAAAUACAGAGUUUCACCCCAGUAAAAUAAACUUCCACGUGAGAGUUGUGUUCAUUCAAGGGUUAUUUUUUGAGAGUGGAAGUACAUUUCCUGCAUUUGUCACAGAUAAUAUCAGAAAUUUUGUUGUUUUGAUUAAAAUGUUGCCAUCUACUUAUAAGUUAAAAAUGCUGAGAAGGUUUUUUUUGGAAACAGUUUAUGAGGCCAGGACAUUUUUAAGUUUGACUCAAAUAUAAAAAGCCACAGUAUUCUUGCCAUGGUUUUGUACUUAGAUGUCUCUCAUUAUGGAAUUCAGAAUGUGACAGUUAUAGUACUACAUGAAAAUACUUAAUAUAGAGUUCUACAGUUACAGUAUUGCAUGAAAAUACAGUAUGGUAUGAAAUUAUUUGUCCAAAACUGUACUCCAGAAAUGGAGCCCAUAUGAUUAUAUAACUAUAAAAUAGGAUGGGACAGAGAAAAAUAUGUCUGUAUUACAGCAUAAACAUAUCUGGUUUAAUAUGAACUAUUUCUUUUCAUCUCUUUACUCUCAGUAUCUCCAUAAUGGCCAGUAUGUAGUAGGCACCUGUAAUUGUGAAGCAGCCUCAUUGUCUGGGGUAAAUACCAAGGUUCUUGGUCUCAUGGCCAAGGAGAUCGAGGUCGCAGACACACACAGUUUGGAGCAGGAGUUUAAUAGGCAAAAGGAAACAGCUCUGUUACAGAGAGGGGUUCCGAGCAGGUUGCCAAGUUGUAGUAAAAAUGUCAGGGUUUUUAUAAAUGGGCUAGUGAGGAGGGGGCUCAUGAGGAGGGGAUAUCUUAUCCUCCUAGGGUCCGAGGACGCUUUAGUUGGGACCAGGUGUGCUAUCUGUACAGAGCAUAGCUUUUUAUCAGCUCUUAUCCCAUUCCUUGACCACAUAGGCUCUUAGACUCUUAUUCUAUGUUGUCUUCGUCCAGCUUAUCUGGAAGGGAGAGUUUCUCUGUCUGUUCCCAUACAUCUUGCAGCUGCAGGCAUCCCCCCGGUCUGCUUUUAGCUUCCUUAUCUUAGUGCCCCUAAAGGGAAAGGAAUGUGCUUAUUAAGGGCCACUGUUUUACUGGGGUUAACUGCAUGAGGUCAAAAAGAGCUAUAUUUGAGCUGCUGUUUGUUAAAAGAAAAGUUUUCUGCCGGGGACUCGCUUUACCCUGUCUACCUAAAUUCUUUCUGCCUUCUAUAACAAUUGUAUGCUCAGUAAAUACAUAAGGAAUAAUGAACUUAAUAACAUUUUUUUCCAUUCUCAAAAUGAUACUUAAAUGACUCAGUACAACAAAGAAACUGAGUAGUAACCAGUGCAAAACUAGCAAAAGGAUGAAAUACACAAGAAAAUGAGAGAAUUUAAGAGGAGUAGCAAAACAGCACUGCUAAAGUUACGGGUUUAUUUUAAAGUUUAAAAUAGAAGUAAACAAGCAAACAUACUGAUAAUGGUUAGGCUUUCUGUCCCCACCGCACAAAUCUCAUCUUGAAUUAUAAUCUCAACAUGUUAAGGGAGAGACCAGAUGAAAGUAAUUGGAUCAUGGGGUUGGUUUCUCCCAUGCUGUUCUCGUGAUAGUUCCCAUGAGAUCUGAUGGUUUUAUAAGUAUUUGGUAGUUCCUCCUGCAUUCAUUCUUCCUGCUGCCCUGUGAAGAGGUGCCUUCCACCAUGAUUGUGAGUUUCUGGAGGCUUCUGCAGCCUUGCGGAACUGUGAGUCAAUCCUUUUUAUUAUAAAUUACCCCGUCUCAGGCAGUUCUUUAUAGCAGUGUGGGGAUGGACUAAUACUCGCUGGGUUAGCUGGGGUAGGUAAAGCCACAGCUGUGGCAGCAACCAGCUAGUGGGUGUCCCUUGAUGGAGGCUUUGCAGGCUGCAGCAGAAGGGACCCUUCAGAUAAACCUCCAGUCAGGAAAGGAAAAGGCCCAAAUAAACAGUAUUUAGAUUUUUUUUUAAAGGACAUAACUACCAAUAGAGAUUUAAAAUAAUCAUAAGAAUACCAUUAACUUUAUGAUAAAAAUUUUGUAAGUGGAGAAGAAAUGGAUAUAUUUCUAGGAAAACAGUAGAAGAUCCAUCUAAGAUUUUGACAAUUUAAAUCAACCACUAAGGAAGUGGAAUCAGUAAUCACAAGUCCACCUCGCCAAAAGACAAUUUUUGAAAGAUGAAUGUUACCAAAACAUCAAGAAACUGAUAAUUCCUGUCUUAUAGAAACUUUGAAAUGAGAGAAAGCUACCCAACCCAUUUCAGAAAGUUAGUAAAAUCUCAAAGCUACACUUGAGCAAAGACUGUGAAAUAUUAAUAGACCAAUCUUGUUUAUGAACAUAGAUGGAAAAAUUGCUGAUGAAAUAUUGGCACAUUGAAUGUAGCAGUGCAUAAAAUAUUGUAUCAUGAGCAAAAGGAGAAUCUUUCCCAGGAACAGGAGGAUGUUUUAAUAAAAAUAUGUAAUUUACCUCUCUACAGAUUAAAGGAGAAAAACUAUAUGAUCACAUCAACAGAAACAGGAAAUUCAGUUUCUUUGGGGGAUAGUUGUAAUUAAAAGUGCUUAACUCACUUAUAUAAGCCAUUAGUGGAUGUUACAAUAAACCUCGUAUAGUGUCAGAUGUAAGACAGACAUACUGGAAUUGUCUAUGAGGUUGGAUCCAUGGGCCUGCCAUGGAAAAUUUGUUGAGUAAUACGUCCAAGGCGUCACCAUUUGCCAGGCGUUGCAAGUAUCACCAUUUGCAAGGUGUUAACAAAAAGUUACCUGCCUAUGGAUUCUCCUUUCUAACUCUGACCUAAUAUUUUGGAGCAUAGAGGAAAGAAACAUCUUAUGUUUCUGUGUUUGGGUAAACAUUAGACUUAUAAAAGGGCCUAGGGUUUUUUUGUUUGGUAAACCAUUGCCUUUCCUGCUUUGGUGUGGCAAAUCUUCCUUUGGAGAAAAAGGUCCCUUUAAUCUUAAAACCAACUCUCAGUGACCAACAAAAGCAACAAAUAGGAACAACCACCCAUUAAGAACCAUCAGGUGAUGCCUCAUUUGCUGUGGUGCACAGCUGAACUUGAUUGUUACUCUUGGAUCAGGGUUGGCUUGAUAAGGACUCACUUAACCAAUGGAAAGUAAGGUUAAAUCUUUGUAAGCAAUGCUCCUGAUGCGAAUCACCUGGAGAUCUUGAGCAAAUGCAGACUGGUUCAGCAGAUCUGGAGUGGGGCCUGAGAUUCUGCAUUUCUAACAAGUUUCCUGGUGAUAUUAAUGCUGCUGGUCUGUGAGCCAUACUUUGAGUAGCAAAGGACUAAAGGUUGUGAGAUAAACUGCUUUUAGCAGCCCAAAGGGCCAGCUGGAAAGACGAGACCAGUUACAGAGCAAAUGGCAAGACAGAUCUGGUAAUCUGAUUCUUAGAGUACUUAAAAAAGAUAAGAAGGAUCUAUUCCUGAUAUACAGGGUACUUGGUGGAUGUGUCCAUGACCUCGAGAUCGAAAACCCAUUAGUUAAUCUUUGUGACAUCUGAAUUUUAAGGAUCUUACCCAGUGAACAUAUAACUAGUGGAAAUCCUGAUAAUUGGCUAAUGCAAGGAAGUGAUACCCAUGUGUAAUGCUUAUCUUUGUAUCCAUUUCAUGGGGAAGGUCAUGGAAGACGACAGCAAACUUGAGUGGUUAAUGAGAGCUUCACUAAUGUUGUCUGCUGCAGGCAAUAAGUGAAGUCUCUGGCAGUGGGAAGCAUGGACCCAAGACCGAAAGCUCUGGCACUUUAUAGCAGUGGUGGGGGGUAGAUAGGACUUAGUGUGGCCCCUUAAAGAGCAAGGUCCAAGUGAUUUUCUCUGGUGAAUGUCGAUGUGGAUCUAGUCUCCAGGGUUAGAUCCAGGCAGGUAACAUCAAAGUCAGUUGAUAAGACCUCUUAUGCCUGUGAAUGGAAGGCCCUGAUAAAACUUCAUUAUUAAUGUUCUGCAUUAAUUUAGCGGAUGACUAUAGUCAUUUCACAUAAUCUAAUACAUGAAUGUCCUGUAUGGGUGACUGCUGAGGGUUUAACAAAGGAGAGUCCAUUUAUAUUUGGCUGGUAAGAUCGAUGCUUCUGUCACUACUGAUGGGCAAGGAUAUUAACAUCAAUAUCUAAAAAAAUUCUGAGAUUUGGAUUGUGAUGUGUUAAAUUUCUAGACCAAUUUGAGGAGAAUUUAACAAUAGCUUUUCAAUUUAUGAACAUGGCGUAUAUCUUUUUUGGCGGGGGGUGAGGACAGAGUCUUGCUCUGAGAUUACCCAGGCUGGAGUUUAGUAGCAUGAUCUUGGCUCACUGCAACCUCUGCCUCCUGAGUUGAAGCAAUUCUCCUGCCUCAGCCUCCCCAGUAGCUGGGAUUACAGGCGAGCGCCAUCAUGCCUGACUAAUUUUCGUAUUUUUAGCAGAGACAGGGUGUCGCCACCUCAAGGGAUCCACCUGCCUUGGCCUCCCAAAGUGCUGGGAUUUAUAAGCGUGAGUCACCGUACCUGGCCAGACAUAGCAUAUAUCUUCCUUUACAUAGAUUGCCUUUGAUUUCUUUCAUUGUUACUUUGUAGUUUUCAGCUUACAGAUUCCGCGCAUAUUUUGUUAGACUUAAAUCUAAGUAUUUGCUUUUUUUUUAACUUACAAAUUUUUUUAAAAAAACGUUUUUCCUCUCCAAUGUUCAUUGCUAAUACAUUUCACGUUUGAAUCUCCAGUUCAGAAAAAUCAUGGCCUCUGGAGUUUUACUGAGGACUAGAGAUAGCUAAGUAACAUAGUUCCACCUUAUUCACUUGGUCUUUGAUGUGGUGUCCAUAAUUGAGUAAAUGGCAGUAUGUCCAAUGGCAACACCAUGAACUUGACUUUGCCCUCUUGUCUAGCCCUCUCCAUUUAGACUUGGAAGGGUCAGCAGUAAAAUUUCACUGGCCCAGUCCAGGGCUGCUUGAGUGUUACUGUUUUGUGCCACAAUAUGAUGUGGCCAGACUACUUUUCUAGUUUCGAGAUUAUUUUGGAGCUUUAUAUUGGGUAUGUUCUUAUCCAACUAUCAUUAGGGGCAUUGAUCUCUGAUGCCCUUUUCUUUCUUAUCUUCCAAAUGGCAGGCAGUAAAUGGCUUAUUAAGCAAGUAUAAGAUUCAAGAUCUCAGCCCCAAAGAUACAUUUGUAGAUGCCAGGCUUAACAUUCCUGAGGCUCUCAGAGAAAACUUUUCCCUCUAUAGACUCCCCAUUUUAAGAAGGAGGCACAGGGCUUGGUUGGCCCAUUUAGUUAGUGACACACCUAUAUUACUCUCCUUGGCAUCUUACCCCAGCCCAUCCAUUGGGUUGUGUCAGUCUUUUAUUUCUAAGUGAGGAUCCAGUCAACAGGAGGCACAAGAGAUAGAACCAAAUACCAUAAUGCCUCCUUCUAUUCCACUAUGAACAGUCAAGGACACUGGAGGCCUCUGGGUGGGACACAUAGGCGUUCAAGAGCCUCUGAGCUUAAAGAUAUGUGAGUGGAGCUAACUAGACUGUCCAGGUUUGGUCUACACUGUAAUUUUUUUUUUUUUUUUUUUUUUUUGGAAGCAGAGUCUUGCUCUUUUGCCCAGGCCAGAGUGUAGUGGUGUGAUCUCAGCUCAGUGCAGCGUCUGCUUCCUGGGUUCAAGUGAUUCUCCUGCCUCAGCCUCCAAGUAGCUGGGACUACAGGUGCCUGCCACCAUGCCCAGCUAAUUUUUGUAUUUUUAGUAGAGACGGGGUUUCACCGUGUUGGCCAGGCUGGUCUCGAACUCCUGAGCUCAAGUGAUCCUCCUGCCUUGGCCUCCCAAAGUGUUGGGAUAGCAGGCAUGAACCACCGUGCUCAGCCUCUCUGUAAAUCUUGAGUCGGCACUGAGCUCAUGAAAGCUGUGCUGAGUGGGUUUCUUUAGAUUUUCAUUUUCAUGUUUGCCCCAUUUAUGCUAAUAUUAAUUAUUGGAAAAUAAUUCACCUACUUUGCUUCUCUCUGACCAACAUAGGGGCAGGAUCUGUGGAAAGACAUUUACCACCUGUUUGAAAAGGUCAGCGUGCUGAUAUUCACUAACUACUACCCCCACAACUCCCCCUCCCCCAAACCUGAUAGAUGCUAUAAUUUCUGCAGUCCAAUCACUAUUCUUCCCAAACUCCAUGAGCCAGAUUUUAUACAUACUUUGCGUGACCAUAAAACUCUGUACUAUUAUAGACAUAAAACCAUUUAAUUUCAUAGAUACCUUCAGUGGUGGCAUCACUGGGUCCUCUCUUGGAUAGCAUAGUCCUAUGACCAAAUGGGUCAGUCGUUGAUCAGGCUUCAUGAGAAUAUGAUCGCUGGGAGAAAUAUACAGCUAAUUUAACAACAAAUGACUGUCCUAAUUCUGGAGACCUGGGAAGUAUUGAUGAGAGUAUAGUGAUCAUAAGCAGACAUUGGGUGCUUUAGCAAAGCCAAUUUGCCUGCAUCCUCUGGAAGGUAAAGAAGAUCUCCUCUCUCUUAGAACUUAAUCAAACUCUUGGCAUCCACAGAAGGCUAGGAGGAUGUAAUGAAUACUUACCAUUUUUGUGGAAGCCCACAACCUUUUGAAUGGCCUUUCUAUACUUUAGUGAACCUCCAUGUUAUGAACCUUACUUCCUCAAGUCUCUUUUGCUGCUAGGAGGCAGACAGUAACUUCGGUAAUUAGAAACAUCUGCACUCAGCAACAUGAAGCACAAGUUCUGUGCAGUUGUCCAUAUGCUGUCAUGAGUUUUGCCAUAUGUAUCAUCUGGCUUUCAGAGGACCUUUCAUGGUUGUCAGGUUAAGUUCCUGAUACAGAAGUGGCAUCAGUGCUGGUGUUAAUGGCUGCAGUAAAGUCAAAUUCCUAGAUUUUAGUGCUCUGUGGUAGCAGAGAGAAUGGUGGUAGUUUAUUUUUUCUUUCCUUUUUUUUUUAAAAAAAAAAAAAAACCUUUUUCAUGUUGAAGUUCACAUGACCUACAACUAACCAUUUUAAAGUGUAAUUCAGUGUCAUUCAGUACAUCCACAAUGUGCAAUCACCACCUCUGUCUAGUUCCAAAACAUUUUUAUCACCCUAAAAGGAAACCUUGCACCCAUUAAACAGUGGUAGUUUCUCUAUCAUGCCACUUUUGUAGCAUGCUUUGGGGUCUUAUUCCUGGGAUCUUUCUCUACAGUGGUAUGAUUAUAUAAGGGUGGAAAUAUAAAAGAGUAAGCCUUUAGAAACAGUUUGUGUCUAAAUUAGCUCUCAGGCAUAUUGUCUUCAAAGGAAUGUUUUAAACCAGCCAAAGACUAACAUCAACAUGCUUACAUUUUGAGUCCAAAAUUAAAAUCCAAAAUAGCCAAGCAUGGUGGCUCACGCCUAUAAUCCCAACUACUCCAGAGGCUGAGGUGUGAUAGAAUUUCUUGAACCUAGGCGUUCCAGGCUGCAGUGAGCUAUGAUUGUGCUGCUGCACUCCAGCCUGGGUGACAGAGCGAGGUUGCUUCUAAAACAAAAAUUUGAAAUAGUAAGUGCUUUGAUUUUUUUUAAUAUAGAAUCAAACAAUUGUGAAAAUAUAAUUGGCUAAGUUUCAUAUACAGUUCUUUCUAAAACUCCUUCUGUUCUCUAAGAUGUAGUUUGAACCAGCCAAGGAUGAUGGCUUCAACAUGUCUCCAGUUGUUUUGCCACUCCAGGGCCUGACUCAAACCAAAAUAAGACUUGCUGUUACCCUGAGACAAGCCAACUGUCAUUGCUUUAGCAACCACUACGGCUACAGGUUGUUGCAUCAUGCCAAGCUCUGUGUUCUUUCUAACUAGUAGAAUGGAGUGGGAUGGUAUCGUGAUGGUGAACCCAAAACAAUGGUACUAGGAAGGAGGUUGGCCAAACUCAGAGUGGAGGCUGACCCUGUAUCUGGUUGUAGCAGAGUCGGUCCUAGGGGAACAGGCUCAGCAGCAGCAAGGAUGCAAGGACCAGAAGGCAGCAGGGGAAGGAAAAGGAGCAGGGGAUAGGGGAACUUUAGGAGCAGAGUAGUGUUGAUAACUGGCAUCUGGAACCUACAGUUUCCAGUUCAGAGCAGUACACCAUACUCAGUGUAUACUUACACUCCAAGACAUUUCCUGGGCAGUGAUCUAGAAAUGAUAUUUUUAAAAGGAGCUGUGUUUCAGUGUUAGACUGUAGUUAUCCAAGCAGUAUCAGAUAGUGUGCAGUUUUUGUAGUAAAAGGUAAAAAUCUGAAUAAUAAAGUUUAUUAAUAACAGUUUUAGUUAAUACUUGACUGACAUUGAGACCCUUGAUGCAAAAAGGUAAGUAGAAGAGAAGGCUGUAAACACAAGACCAUCAUACCCUGUGGGGAAUUUACAAUCUAAAUAUAACAAACAUAUAGAGUGAGAUAGGAGAAAAGAAAUGGGAUGAUAAUGAUAUUGCUGUACUAAAGUCUAUUUAGGAAAUGGAAAUAUAUAGCAAGAGGAGUCAGCUACUUGGGCAUUGAUCAAAGAAAAAUAAACAUAUAGAAGGAAAGAAAGGUCGUUUUAGUUUAUAACAUUUUCCUUCCGAUUCUAGGUGAUUAUAUAGCUAGUUUACUCUUCCACCCCCAAGAUUCUGGGGUAUUUUGGCUAAUGUUAUUUGCAAUGUCCAUAAACUCAGAAGAAGUUAGUAUUAACGGGGAUAUGAAAGAACCUCCAGUUACUAUGCAAGAAAUUUUAAAUUUCCAUCAUGUUAAAUUGUACAACUGUUUAUCAUUCACUCUGCUGUAAGUCUAUGUGAAACCAAAUCCGUGGAUUUACCAAUGGCCAUUUUAUCACCUCCAAACUAUCUUUUAUUUUUUUGAAUUGUAUCUCUCUCCUUAUUCCAUUUUCUUCUGUUUGAUUAAAAUCCUGCAUGUUCUCCUGCA